GUUCCCCUUCCCCGGCUCUAGCAGGCCGGCUUCUCUGUCCAAUGCCCACCCGGAGCUGGGAGGAGGAGUCUGCGUAAUGUGCGUGUGAAGAGACUGGGGGAGCUGGCCGGGGCUCACGGUGUUUGACCCGUCGGUCGUGCGUGAGAGGAAAGGGAAGGAGGAGGUCCCGAAUAGCGGUCGCCGAAAUGUUCCGGUGUGGAGGCCUGGCGGCGGGUGCUUUGAAGCAGAAGCUGGUGCCCUUGGUGCGGACCGUGUGCGUCCGAAGCCCGAGGCAGAGGAACCGGCUCCCAGGCAACUUGUUCCAGCGAUGGCAUGUUCCUCUAGAACUCCAGAUGACAAGACAAAUGGCUAGCUCUGGUGCAUCAGGGGGCAAAAUCGAUAAUUCUGUGUUAGUCCUUAUUGUGGGCUUAUCAACAGUAGGAGCUGGUGCCUAUGCCUACAAGACUAUGAAAGAGGAUGAAAAAAGAUACAAUGAAAGAAUUUCAGGGUUAGGGCUGACACCAGAACAGAAACAGAAAAAGGCCGCGUUAUCUGCUUCAGAAGGAGAGGAAGUUCCUCAAGACAAGGCGCCAAGUCAUGUUCCUUUCCUGCUAAUUGGUGGAGGCACAGCUGCUUUUGCUGCAGCCAGAUCCAUCCGGGCUCGGGAUCCUGGGGCCAGGGUACUGAUUGUAUCUGAAGAUCCUGAGCUGCCGUACAUGCGACCUCCUCUUUCAAAAGAACUGUGGUUUUCAGAUGACCCAAAUGUCACAAAGACACUGCGAUUCAAACAGUGGAAUGGAAAAGAGAGAAGCAUAUAUUUCCAGCCACCUUCUUUCUAUGUCUCUGCUCAGGACCUGCCUCAUAUUGAGAAUGGUGGUGUGGCUGUCCUCACUGGGAAGAAGGUAGUACAGCUGGAUGUGAGAGACAACAUGGUGAAACUUAAUGAUGGCUCUCAAAUAACCUAUGAAAAGUGCUUGAUUGCAACAGGAGGUACUCCAAGAAGUCUGUCUGCCAUUGAUAGGGCUGGAGCAGAGGUGAAGAGUAGAACAACGCUUUUCAGAAAGAUUGGAGACUUUAGAAGCUUGGAGAAGAUUUCACGGGAAGUCAAAUCAAUUACGAUUAUCGGUGGGGGCUUCCUUGGUAGCGAACUGGCCUGUGCUCUUGGCAGAAAGGAUAUAUGAAAUCAGGGCAUCUUUUCAGGAGGAUGCUUCCUAUUCAGAGGUUGCAAAGCACUUAUGUAAGCCUUAGGUGACUGCAUGGGUGGAAGUGCACAGAGUUCACCAUCUGAAGCUUAAUCUGGGGCCAGCAGUUCUGAUACCUGUUGUAUUUGCGUUACAAAUGAACUUGAGCACCGAGGCCCUCAUGCCCACUGUCCUCUCGAGCCUUGGGCACAGAAGUGAUUCAACUCUUCCCCGAGAAAGGAAAUAUGGGAAAGAUCCUCCCCGAAUACCUCAGCAACUGGACCAUGGAAAAAGUCAGACGAGAGGGGGUUAAGGUGAUGCCCAAUGCUAUUGUGCAAUCCGUUGGAGUCAGCAGUGGCAAGUUACUUAUCAAGCUGAAAGACGGCAGGAAGGUAGAAACUGACCACAUAGUGGCAGCUGUGGGCCUGGAGCCCAAUGUUGAGUUGGCCAAGACUGGUGGCCUGGAAAUAGACUCAGAUUUUGGUGGCUUCCGGGUAAAUGCAGAGCUACAAGCACGCUCUAACAUCUGGGUGGCAGGAGAUGCUGCAUGCUUCUACGAUAUAAAGUUGGGAAGGAGGCGGGUAGAGCACCAUGAUCACGCUGUUGUGAGUGGAAGAUUGGCUGGAGAAAAUAUGACUGGAGCUGCUAAGCCGUACUGGCAUCAGUCAAUGUUCUGGAGUGAUUUGGGCCCCGAUGUUGGCUAUGAAGCUAUUGGUCUUGUGGACAGUAGUUUGCCCACAGUUGGUGUUUUUGCAAAAGCAACUGCACAAGACAACCCCAAAUCUGCCACAGAGCAGUCAGGAACUGGUAUCCGAUCAGAGAGUGAGACAGAGUCCGAGGCCUCAGAAAUUACUAUUCCUCCCAGCACCCCGGCAGUUCCACAGGCUCCCGUCCAGGGGGAGGACUACGGCAAAGGUGUCAUCUUCUACCUCAGGGACAAAGUGGUCGUGGGGAUUGUGCUAUGGAACAUCUUUAACCGAAUGCCAAUAGCAAGGAAGAUCAUUAAGGACGGUGAGCAGCAUGAAGAUCUCAAUGAAGUAGCCAAACUAUUCAACAUUCAUGAAGACUGAAGCCCCACAGUGGAAUUGGCAAACCCACUGCAGCCCCUGAGAGGAGGUCGAAUGGGUAAAGGAGCAUUUUUUUAUUCAGCAGACUUUCUCUGUGUAUGAGUGUGAAUGAUCAAGUCCUUUGUGAAUAUUUUCAACUAUGUAGGUAAAUUCUUAAUGUUCACAUAGUGAAAUAAAUUCUGAUUCUUCUAAAUUAAA